GGGCUGUCCUAAAACCAGAAGCUUGGAGCAGAAAGUGAAACCCUGGUGCUCCAGACAAAGAUCUUAGUCGGGACUAGCCGGCCAAGGAUGAAGCCUCACUUCAGAAACACAGUGGAGCGAAUGUAUCGAGACACAUUCUCCUACAACUUUUAUAAUAGACCCAUCCUUUCUCGUCGGAAUACCGUCUGGCUGUGCUACGAAGUGAAAACAAAGGGUCCCUCAAGGCCCCCUUUGGACGCAAAGAUCUUUCGAGGCCAGGUGUAUUCCGAACUUAAGUACCACCCAGAGAUGAGAUUCUUCCACUGGUUCAGCAAGUGGAGGAAGCUGCAUCGUGACCAGGAGUAUGAGGUCACCUGGUACAUAUCCUGGAGCCCCUGCACAAAGUGUACAAGGGAUAUGGCCACGUUCCUGGCCGAGGACCCGAAGGUUACCCUGACCAUCUUUGUUGCCCGCCUCUACUACUUCUGGGACCCAGAUUACCAGGAGGCGCUUCGCAGCCUGUGUCAGAAAAGAGACGGUCCGCGUGCCACCAUGAAGAUCAUGAAUUAUGACGAAUUUCAGCACUGUUGGAGCAAGUUCGUGUACAGCCAAAGAGAGCUAUUUGAGCCUUGGAAUAAUCUGCCUAAAUAUUAUAUAUUACUGCACAUCAUGCUGGGGGAGAUUCUCAGGUGAGGGUCUCCCUCCAGGCUCAUCGCCUCGCUCCUCUCACCUCCUGCUCAUCCUCUUGAGGCCUCCCCUCUGUUCCAGACCAGGUCCUCUCCUGGCCAGGCCCUCCUGCCUUCCCUCCUGCCCCCUGCCUGCCCUCGUGGUUACACUCCCUCACCCACACUCCUCGUGCUCCCUCCACCUCCCUGCCUCCCACCUGCUUUCCUGGGCCCUUCCUGUGAGUGAGAGGCCCCUUCUGCCUCCAGAGCAACCUCCAUCCACCCCCACAGCCUGGGAGCCCCAACCUGGCCCCUUCCAUCUCCCUGGCAUAACCGAAUUUGUCGUAAAACUGGACGUAGUAAGUGGGCAUGAAUAGUCACAAGCCCGGCAGUCAGAAGCUUUGAGCAACAUCCUUAAAGGCCAACCUGAGCCCCUGAGAAGGAGCUGCCUCCAUGGAAACAGAGCUUCAGGCUUCGGCUGCCAUAGAAGAUGGCCGGGCUGGGUGCCCACAGGGCAGGCAUUUAUUUUCUCACACAUCUGGAGGCUGCAAGUCCAAGGUGGAGGGGUGGGCGGGGUUGUGUCUUCUGCAGUCGCUCCUCCUGGCUGGCAGGGGGUCCCUUCCGGCCCUGUCCUCUCUGGCCUUUCCUCUGUGCACCUGCACUCGUGGGGUCUCUCUGCCUCCAAAUGUCCUCCUCGUUUAUGGACCCCAGUCAUGUGAAUUUGGGCCCACACUGAAGGUCUCAUUUAAGUUAAUCAUCUGAUGAAAGGACCUGUCUCCAGGCCAGGUGCAGAGGCUCAUGCCUGUAAUCCCAGCACUUUGGGAGUCCAAGGCGGGUGGAUCACCUGAGGUCAGGAGUUCGACACCAGCCUGGCCAACAUGUUAAAACCCCAUCUCUACCAAAAAUACAAAAAUUAGCCGGGAGUGGUGGUGGGCGCCUAUAAUUCUAGCUACUCGGAAGGCUGAGGCAGGAGAAUCGCUUGAACCCGGGAGGCGGAGGUUGCGGUGAGCCCAGACUGCGCCGCUGCACUCCAGCCUGGGCAAAAAAGCGAAACUUCUUCUCAAACAAACAAACAAGAAAGAAAGGACCUGUUUCCAAAUACAGCCACCCUUUGAGGGAGCGGGGGUUAAGGCUUCAAUACAUUGAUUUUGGGGAGAAACAGUGAAGGCCACGGCAAGAAGCUGCAGUCAUUGUGGGCGGGCCUGGGUGGGGAGUGCAGGGGUUCCUGUCCUGUGUGUCUGUUUCCCAGGGGAGUCCUGACCUGACUCUCACAGCCCCUCCACCCAGAUGUUCCUGUGUGCUUCACCCACCCCAUUCCUUCUGCACCCAACACUCCUGAGCCCCUCCUUAGCUCCCCCGACAGGCUCCCCUGCUCCCCCACUCCCGGGCUGCUCCUCUUCUCAGCCUCUCUCUGGGCCUCUCUGGGGUCCGGACAUGACCCCUCAGCUGAUGCCUGUGGCUUCCCCAGCCAGAAUCUUCCCAGUUCCAGGCUGGGCUCUGCAGAGUCCUAUCAAAGGUGGCAUCCUCCCCUCUGUCCACUCCAGGGUGAAGAUCUGGUGUUUCUGGUUUGGAAAUGCCUCUGCACUGGGUGCUAAUAAUUCACUUUUACCUUUA